AGACUCCUGCGGAUGCCAUUAUGAGGAGCAAGAACGCGAAGGGGCCUCGGGUCCGCUAGGCCGGGAUCCGGAGCCGCCCGAAGCCGGUGCCGCAGCCCCCUGCGCCCCCGGUGCCCCCGACAUGUCCUUCCGCAAAGUGGUCCGGCAGAGCAAAUUCCGGCAUGUGUUCGGGCAGCCGGUCAAGAACGACCAGUGCUAUGAGGACAUUCGCGUGUCCCGUGUUACCUGGGACAGCACCUUCUGCGCCGUCAACCCCAAGUUCCUGGCGGUGAUUGUGGAGGCCAGUGGAGGGGGUGCCUUUCUGGUGCUCCCCCUAAGCAAGACGGGCCGCAUUGACAAGGCCUACCCGACGGUGUGUGGGCACACGGGACCUGUCCUGGACAUCGACUGGUGUCCUCACAACGACGAAGUCAUAGCCAGCGGCUCGGAGGACUGCACGGUCAUGGUGUGGCAGAUCCCAGAGAACGGGCUGACCUCCCCGCUGACAGAGCCGGUGGUGGUACUGGAGGGGCACACCAAGCGAGUGGGCAUCAUCGCCUGGCACCCCACGGCCCGAAACGUGCUGCUCAGUGCAGGCUGCGACAACGUGGUACUCAUCUGGAAUGUGGGCACAGCGGAGGAGCUGUACCGCCUGGACAGCCUGCACCCUGACCUCAUCUACAAUGUCAGCUGGAACCACAAUGGCAGCCUGUUUUGCUCAGCAUGCAAGGACAAGAGCGUGCGCAUCAUCGACCCCCGUCGGGGCACCCUGGUGGCAGAGCGGGAGAAGGCUCAUGAGGGGGCCCGGCCCAUGCGGGCCAUCUUCCUGGCAGAUGGCAAGGUGUUCACCACAGGCUUCAGCCGAAUGAGCGAGCGGCAGCUGGCGCUCUGGGACCCAGAAAACCUCGAGGAACCCAUGGCCCUGCAGGAACUGGACUCGAGCAACGGGGCCCUGCUGCCCUUCUACGACCCCGACACCAGUGUGGUCUACGUCUGCGGCAAGGGUGACUCCAGCAUCCGGUACUUUGAGAUCACAGAGGAGCCUCCCUACAUCCACUUCCUGAACACGUUCACCAGCAAGGAGCCGCAGCGGGGUAUGGGCAGCAUGCCCAAGCGGGGCCUGGAGGUCAGCAAGUGCGAGAUCGCCCGGUUCUACAAACUGCAUGAGCGCAAGUGUGAGCCCAUCGUCAUGACUGUGCCAAGAAAGUCGGACCUCUUCCAGGAUGAUCUGUACCCCGACACAGCCGGGCCCGAGGCAGCCCUGGAGGCUGAGGAGUGGGUGAGCGGGCGGGAUGCCGACCCGAUCCUCAUCUCACUGCGGGAGGCCUACGUGCCCAGCAAGCAGCGGGACCUGAAGAUCAGCCGGCGCAACGUGUUGUCUGACAGCCGGCCCGCCAUGGCCCCGGGCUCCUCCCACCUAGGGGCCCCCGCCUCCACCACCACUGCUGCUGAUGCCACCCCCAGCGGCAGCCUGGCCAGAGCCGGGGAGGCUGGGAAGCUGGAGGAGGUGAUGCAGGAGCUGCGGGCCCUGAGGGCGCUGGUCAAGGAGCAGGGCGACCGCAUCUGCCGCCUGGAGGAGCAGCUGGGCCGCAUGGAGAACGGGGAUGCGUAGGGCCACAGCCACACGCCACCUUCAUCUCCUCCGCCGCCCCCUUCCCACUCAGCUUCUGCCAGCGGGUCGCACCGGGCUAGCUGGCUGCCCAGAGCCUCUGAGGCAGCGCAGGGGUCAGUUCCCACCCCCACCCGUCCCAGGCCCAGGCCGAAGCCAGCGCCCAGCUUUCCUCACUGUUCCUGUGGAGGAUGUCUACGCCCAGGCGAGCUCCUCGACCUCUGAGGGACCAUCUCCCCGACCACUGCCCAGCCCUCUGCUCCCUCCCCAGAGGAGGCGGGAGGGUGGGCUCUAUAUUUUCAUUCCAAAUAAAAUUCUCUUUCUAAAAGCCAGGCUGACCUGCUGCUGCAAGGGUGGGGCUGAGAAGUCUGGAAACCUGGAGACAGAGGAUGUCACAGGAGUCACACAUGUGCAGAAGGUCUGGGGGCAGUGAGCAGCCCCACAGGCAUUGCUCCCCUGGAUUGUCAGGCAGGGAAACUGAGGCAGAAGACCUGAGAACACAUGCAAGGCUGCAUCCAGCUUCAAGUUGGUGCUGCUUCUUCCUUGGAGGACAGGCCCGGCAGCCCAGCCUCCUCCAGAGAGACUGGGGAGGGUCUGGUGUGGACCAGGGGUCCUGCAGCAGGGAGGGGCAGGUGGGGUAUGUGGGCAGGAAGCGGAAGCCUGGGCCACCCUUCACUGCAGACGAGCACUGAGCUCACUUCUCGCUCGACACAGCCAGAGCUGGAGGUGGGUGCCCGGCACGGAGGGGCCUGCGGACCAAUGGUAAGCCUCGGAGCCCCCCGGGUUCUUGGGAUGGGGGCCACAGGCGGUCGGGGCUAGAAUGUCUGGGCCUGUGGAGCUAAGGAGGGCCCCACAUUGGCCCCAGGGAAGAGGUGAGACCUAAGAGGAGUAUGGCAGAGGCUGAACCUUUCUCUCACCUGAGCUGGGCUCCCUGGGACUCCAGGCCUGGCCCCCAGCACCCCAUACCGGACCAGGCCCCUGUCAGGAGCCCUGGGAAGGCCCUUACCUGGUCUUCCUGUGAGCGGGAACUUGCAUUCCUGGAGCCUGGGCGGACAGCCUGGGGUGGUGGGGGAGGCUGGCUGCACCUCAGCACCCCUCCCCCGACACCCCCCACCUAGCCUGUUCCGACCGCAGACUUCCUCUGGCAGCUGCGCCCGCCUCCCCCAGCCCCCCCCAGCCCCCGGCCCUGCACGCCUGUGGCCCUCAGGGACUGGGAGUGGAACGGAAACCCUGCCGCUGGGGCAGCCCCGUGGUGGGGAGGGAGGAAGAGGGGCCUCACGGACCCCCGUUUGGGGACCUGGCCAAGCAGAAGAUGAGCAGUUGCCUCUGGGUGCAUCCAGGCCCCUCCAUCCCCCAUCCCAGGCCUCAGGGAGAGCCAGCCCUGACACCAGCUAGCAACCUCCUUCCCUCCCUCCCAUCUCCUCUCCCACCCACCCAGGCAGCCUAGACACAUUUAAUCCAUACUUAUUGAGCACCUACUAACAUGCUUGACCCAAAAAGCCCCCGUUUCCUAGCAGCUUAUUGUGGGGGGUAGAUAAGACAAUAGACAUAAAAAAUGAGUACAGUUAUCUCCUGCGUUAGGUGACAUGGAAGGAAAAAGGCACUGAGUGCUGGGGGGUGCUGGGGUGGGCUGCAGUGAUAGACAUCAGGGUAGAGGUUAAGGUCAGGUUCAGCCUCACUGGGGUGAAGUUUGAGCACGGUGAGCAGGCCAUGCAGCCCGGGGGAGGGGAGGAUGGGAGGAGGUGGAGCUUUCCGGGCAGAGGGAACAGCCAGUGCGAAGGCCCCAGGCAGGUGGCUUAAUGCAGCUGUUGGGGGAGGUGAGUGGUAGGGAGGAGGCUGGAGGGAUGGGGGCUGAUCUCACAGGGCCAGAGCCUGGUUGACCAAAUAAGGCCUUGGCCUUUUCUGCUUGGCUGUCCCAAGAGGAUCCCAAAGAGAAAAAAACGAAAGUGGUCUUGGUCACCCAGCCUGCCCCACACCAGGCCCCACCCCAGGUGCUGAGCCCUCUGAGCCCCUGCCUGUCUCCCACAGGCUCUGCCCUGCACCUUAGGGCUCGGGAUGCUGCUGGCCCUGCCAGGGGCCUUGGGCUCGGGUGGCAGCGCGGAGGACAGCGUGGGCUCCAGCUCUGUCACCGUUGUCCUGCUGCUGCUGCUGCUCCUACUGCUGGCCACUGGCCUAGCACUGGCCUGGCGCCGCCUCAGCCGUGACUCAGGGGGCUACUACCACCCGGCCCGCCUAGGUGCCGCGCUGUGGGGCCGCACGCGGCGCCUGCUCUGGGCCAGCCCCCCAGGUCGCUGGCUGCAGGCCCGAGCUGAGCUGGGGUCCACAGACAAUGACCUUGAGCGACAGGAGGAUGAGCAGGACACAGACUAUGACCACGUCGCGGAUGGUGGCCUGCAGGCUGACCCUGGGGAAGGCGAGCAGCAAUGUGGAGAGGCGUCCAGCCCAGAGCAGGUCCCCGUGCGGGCUGAGGAAGCCAGAGACAGUGACACGGAGGGCGACCUGGUCCUCGGCUCCCCAGGACCAGCGAGCGCAGGGGGCAGUGCUGAGGCCCUGCUGAGUGACCUGCACGCCUUUGCUGGCAGCGCAGCCUGGGAUGACAGCGCCAGGGCAGCUGGGGGCCAGGGCCUCCAUGUCACCGCACUGUAGAGGCCGGUCUUGGUGUCCCAUCCCUGUCACAGCCGCUCACUCCCCGUGCCUCUGCUUCCCAAGAUGCCAUGGCUGGACUGGACCCCCAGCCCACAUGACCAUGCCUCAGACUGUCACCCCCUACCAGUUCCCAAGUCCAUGUGUACCCCGCUCACCACGGGAACGGCCCCCCCCAACCACAGGCAUCAGGCAACCAUUUGAAAUAAAACUCCUUCAGCCUGUG